CCCCCUUCGGCCGCGGCGAGGAGGAGCCGGAGCGGGAGUGACACCGAGCCGGACCCAGCGCGACCUGCGGCGGCUCCGGGUGACUCGGGCCAGUGUAGAGGUCCUCAGGCCGCCGGCAGGAGCAGCUGGGCCAAUUCCCUGGCCGGGAGCGGAAGGGGAUGGCGUCGGGCCUGGGCUCCCCGUCCCCCUGCUCGGCGGGCAGUGAGGAGGAGGAUAUGGAUGCACUUUUGAACAACAGCCUGCCCCCACCCCACCCAGAAAAUGAAGAGGACCCAGAAGAGGAUUUGUCAGAAACAGAGACUCCAAAGCUCAAGAAGAAGAAAAAGCCUAAGAAACCUCGGGACCCUAAAAUCCCUAAGAGCAAGCGCCAAAAAAAGGAGCGUAUGCUCUUAUGCCGGCAGCUGGGGGACAGCUCUGGGGAGGGGCCAGAGUUUGUGGAGGAGGAGGAAGAGGUGGCUCUGCGCUCAGACAGUGAGGGCAGCGACUAUACUCCUGGCAAGAAGAAGAAGAAGAAGCUUGGACCUAAGAAAGAGAAGAAGAGCAAAUCCAAGCGGAAGGAGGAGGAGGAGGAGGAGGAUGAUGAUGAUGAUUCAAAGGAGCCUAAAUCAUCUGCUCAGCUCCUGGAAGACUGGGGCAUGGAAGACAUUGACCACGUGUUCUCAGAGGAGGAUUAUCGAACCCUCACCAACUACAAGGCCUUCAGCCAGUUUGUCAGACCCCUCAUUGCUGCCAAAAAUCCCAAGAUUGCUGUCUCCAAGAUGAUGAUGGUUUUGGGUGCAAAAUGGCGGGAGUUCAGUACCAAUAACCCCUUCAAAGGCAGUUCUGGGGCAUCAGUGGCAGCUGCGGCAGCAGCAGCGGUAGCUGUGGUGGAGAGCAUGGUGACAGCCACUGAGGUUGCACCACCACCUCCCCCUGUGGAGGUGCCUAUCCGCAAGGCCAAGACCAAGGAGGGCAAAGGUCCCAAUGCUCGGAGGAAGCCCAAGGGCAGCCCUCGUGUACCUGAUGCCAAGAAGCCUAAACCCAAGAAAGUAGCUCCCCUGAAAAUCAAGCUGGGAGGUUUUGGUUCCAAGCGUAAGAGAUCCUCGAGUGAGGAUGAUGACUUAGAUGUGGAAUCUGACUUCGAUGAUGCCAGUAUCAAUAGCUAUUCUGUUUCUGAUGGUUCCACCAGCCGUAGUAGCCGCAGCCGCAAGAAACUCCGAACCACUAAAAAGAAAAAGAAAGGCGAGGAGGAGGUGACUGCUGUGGAUGGUUAUGAGACAGACCACCAGGACUAUUGCGAGGUGUGCCAGCAAGGCGGUGAGAUCAUCCUGUGUGAUACCUGUCCCCGUGCUUACCACAUGGUCUGCCUGGAUCCCGACAUGGAGAAGGCUCCCGAGGGCAAGUGGAGCUGCCCACACUGCGAGAAGGAAGGCAUCCAGUGGGAAGCUAAAGAGGACAAUUCGGAGGGUGAGGAGAUCCUGGAAGAGGUUGGGGGAGACCUCGAAGAGGAGGAUGACCACCAUAUGGAAUUCUGUCGGGUCUGCAAGGAUGGUGGGGAACUGCUCUGCUGUGAUACCUGUCCUUCUUCCUACCACAUCCACUGCCUGAAUCCCCCACUUCCAGAGAUCCCCAACGGUGAAUGGCUCUGUCCCCGUUGUACGUGUCCAGCUCUGAAGGGCAAAGUGCAGAAGAUCCUAAUCUGGAAGUGGGGUCAGCCACCAUCUCCCACACCAGUGCCUCGGCCUCCAGAUGCUGAUCCCAACACGCCCUCCCCAAAGCCCUUGGAGGGGCGGCCAGAGCGGCAGUUCUUUGUGAAAUGGCAAGGCAUGUCUUACUGGCACUGCUCCUGGGUUUCUGAACUGCAGCUGGAGCUGCACUGUCAGGUGAUGUUCCGAAACUAUCAGCGGAAGAAUGAUAUGGAUGAGCCACCUUCUGGGGACUUUGGUGGUGAUGAAGAGAAAAGCCGAAAGCGAAAGAACAAGGACCCUAAAUUUGCAGAGAUGGAGGAACGCUUCUAUCGCUAUGGGAUAAAACCCGAGUGGAUGAUGAUCCACCGAAUCCUCAACCACAGUGUGGACAAGAAGGGCCACGUCCACUACUUGAUCAAGUGGCGGGACUUACCUUACGAUCAGGCUUCUUGGGAGAGUGAGGAUGUGGAGAUCCAGGAUUACGACCUGUUCAAGCAGAGCUAUUGGAAUCACAGGGAGUUAAUGAGGGGUGAGGAAGGCCGACCAGGCAAGAAGCUCAAGAAGGUGAAGCUUCGGAAGUUGGAGAGGCCUCCAGAAACGCCAACAGUUGAUCCAACAGUGAAGUAUGAGCGACAGCCAGAGUACCUGGAUGCUACAGGUGGAACCCUGCACCCCUAUCAAAUGGAGGGCCUGAAUUGGUUGCGCUUCUCCUGGGCUCAGGGCACUGACACCAUCUUGGCUGAUGAGAUGGGCCUUGGGAAAACUGUACAGACAGCAGUCUUCCUGUAUUCCCUUUACAAGGAGGGUCAUUCCAAAGGCCCCUUCCUAGUGAGCGCCCCUCUUUCUACCAUCAUCAACUGGGAGCGGGAGUUUGAAAUGUGGGCUCCAGACAUGUAUGUCGUAACCUAUGUGGGUGACAAGGACAGCCGUGCCAUCAUCCGAGAGAAUGAGUUCUCCUUUGAAGACAAUGCCAUUCGUGGUGGCAAGAAGGCCUCCCGCAUGAAGAAAGAGGCAUCUGUGAAAUUCCAUGUGCUGCUGACAUCCUAUGAAUUGAUCACCAUUGACAUGGCUAUUUUGGGCUCUAUUGAUUGGGCCUGCCUCAUCGUGGAUGAAGCCCAUCGGCUGAAGAACAAUCAGUCUAAGUUCUUCCGGGUAUUGAAUGGUUACUCACUCCAGCACAAGCUGUUGCUGACUGGGACACCAUUACAAAACAAUCUGGAAGAGUUGUUUCAUCUGCUCAACUUUCUCACCCCCGAGAGGUUCCACAAUUUGGAAGGUUUUUUGGAGGAGUUUGCUGACAUUGCCAAGGAGGACCAGAUAAAAAAACUGCAUGACAUGCUGGGGCCGCACAUGUUGCGGCGGCUCAAAGCCGAUGUGUUCAAGAACAUGCCCUCCAAGACAGAACUAAUUGUGCGUGUGGAGCUGAGCCCUAUGCAGAAGAAAUACUACAAGUACAUCCUCACUCGAAAUUUUGAAGCACUCAAUGCCCGAGGUGGUGGCAACCAGGUGUCUCUGCUGAAUGUGGUGAUGGAUCUUAAGAAGUGCUGCAACCAUCCAUACCUCUUCCCUGUGGCUGCAAUGGAAGCUCCUAAGAUGCCUAAUGGCAUGUAUGAUGGCAGUGCCCUAAUCAGAGCAUCUGGGAAAUUAUUGCUGCUGCAGAAAAUGCUCAAGAACCUUAAGGAGGGUGGGCAUCGUGUACUCAUCUUUUCCCAGAUGACCAAGAUGCUAGACCUGCUAGAGGAUUUCUUGGAACAUGAAGGUUAUAAAUACGAACGCAUCGAUGGUGGAAUCACUGGGAACAUGCGGCAAGAGGCCAUUGACCGCUUCAAUGCACCGGGUGCUCAGCAGUUCUGCUUCUUGCUUUCCACUCGAGCUGGGGGCCUUGGAAUCAAUCUGGCCACUGCUGACACAGUUAUUAUCUAUGACUCUGACUGGAACCCCCAUAAUGACAUUCAGGCCUUUAGCAGAGCUCACCGGAUUGGGCAAAAUAAAAAGGUAAUGAUCUACCGGUUUGUGACCCGUGCGUCAGUGGAGGAGCGCAUCACGCAGGUGGCAAAGAAGAAAAUGAUGCUGACGCAUCUAGUGGUGCGGCCUGGGCUGGGCUCCAAGACUGGAUCUAUGUCCAAACAGGAGCUUGAUGAUAUCCUCAAAUUUGGCACUGAGGAACUAUUCAAGGAUGAAGCCACUGAUGGAGGAGGAGACAACAAAGAGGGAGAAGAUAGCAGUGUUAUCCACUACGAUGAUAAGGCCAUUGAACGGCUGCUAGACCGUAACCAGGAUGAGACUGAAGACACAGAAUUGCAGGGCAUGAAUGAAUAUUUGAGCUCAUUCAAAGUGGCCCAGUAUGUGGUACGGGAAGAAGAAAUGGGGGAGGAAGAGGAGGUAGAACGGGAAAUCAUUAAACAGGAAGAAAGUGUGGAUCCUGACUACUGGGAGAAAUUGCUGCGGCACCAUUAUGAGCAGCAGCAAGAAGAUCUAGCCCGAAAUCUGGGCAAAGGAAAAAGAAUCCGUAAACAGGUCAACUACAAUGAUGGCUCCCAGGAGGACCGAGAUUGGCAGGACGACCAGUCCGACAACCAGUCCGAUUACUCAGUGGCUUCAGAGGAAGGUGAUGAAGACUUUGAUGAACGUUCAGAAGCUCCCCGUAGGCCCAGUCGUAAGGGCCUGCGGAAUGAUAAAGAUAAGCCAUUGCCUCCUCUGUUGGCCCGUGUUGGUGGGAAUAUUGAAGUACUUGGUUUUAAUGCUCGUCAGCGAAAAGCCUUUCUUAAUGCAAUUAUGCGAUAUGGUAUGCCACCUCAGGAUGCUUUUACUACCCAGUGGCUUGUAAGAGACCUGCGAGGCAAAUCAGAGAAAGAGUUCAAGGCAUAUGUCUCUCUUUUCAUGCGGCAUUUAUGUGAGCCGGGGGCAGAUGGGGCUGAGACCUUUGCUGAUGGUGUCCCCCGAGAAGGCCUGUCUCGCCAGCAUGUCCUUACUAGAAUUGGUGUUAUGUCUUUGAUUCGCAAGAAGGUUCAGGAGUUUGAACAUGUUAAUGGGCGCUGGAGCAUGCCUGAACUGGCUGAGGUGGAGGAAAACAAGAAGAUGUCCCAGCCAGGGUCACCCUCCCCAAAAACUCCUACACCCUCCACUCCAGGGGACACGCAGCCCAACACUCCUGCACCUGUCCCACCUGCUGAAGAUGGGAUAAAAAUAGAGGAAAAUAGCCUCAAAGAAGAAGAGAGCAUAGAAGGAGAAAAGGAGGUUAAAUCUACAGCCCCUGAGACUGCCAUUGAGUGUACACAGGCCCCUGCCCCUGCCUCAGAGGAUGAAAAGGUCGUUGUUGAACCCCCUGAGGGAGAGGAGAAAGUGGAAAAGGCAGAGGUGAAGGAGAGAACAGAGGAACCUAUGGAGACAGAGCCCAAAGGUGCUGCUGAUGUAGAGAAGGUGGAGGAAAAGUCAGCAAUAGAUCUGACCCCUAUUGUGGUAGAAGACAAAGAAGAGAAGAAAGAAGAAGAAGAGAAAAAAGAGGUGAUGCUUCAGAAUGGAGAGACCCCCAAGGACCUGAAUGAUGAGAAACAGAAGAAAAAUAUUAAACAACGUUUCAUGUUUAACAUUGCAGAUGGUGGUUUUACUGAGUUGCACUCCCUUUGGCAGAAUGAAGAGCGGGCAGCCACAGUUACCAAGAAGACUUAUGAGAUCUGGCAUCGACGGCAUGACUACUGGCUGCUAGCCGGCAUUAUAAACCAUGGCUAUGCCCGGUGGCAAGACAUCCAGAAUGACCCACGCUAUGCCAUCCUCAAUGAGCCUUUCAAGGGUGAAAUGAACCGUGGCAAUUUCUUAGAGAUCAAGAAUAAAUUUCUAGCUCGAAGGUUUAAGCUCUUAGAACAAGCUCUGGUGAUUGAGGAACAGCUGCGCCGGGCUGCUUACUUGAACAUGUCAGAAGACCCUUCUCACCCUUCCAUGGCCCUCAACACCCGCUUUGCUGAGGUGGAGUGUUUGGCGGAAAGUCAUCAGCACCUGUCCAAGGAGUCAAUGGCAGGAAACAAGCCAGCCAAUGCAGUCCUGCACAAAGUUCUGAAACAGCUGGAAGAACUGCUGAGUGACAUGAAAGCUGAUGUGACUCGACUCCCAGCUACCAUUGCCCGAAUUCCCCCAGUUGCUGUGAGGUUACAGAUGUCAGAGCGUAACAUUCUCAGCCGCCUGGCAAACCGGGCACCCGAACCUACCCCACAGCAGGUAGCCCAGCAGCAGUGAAGAUGCAGACUGAUACCACCUCCACCGCUGAGCAGUGACCUUCCUCACUUUCUCUUGUCCCAGCUUCUCCCCUGGGGGCCUGAGAGACCCUCACCUUCCUUCUGCCCAUCUUCCAUGUUGUAAAGGAACAGCCCCAGUGCACUGGGGGAGGGGAGGGAGUGAGGGGCAGUGGUGCCCUUCCUGCAGAAGAGACAUGCAGCAGUAGCGCUGGCGCCAUCUGCAGGAGCUGGCGGGCUGGCCUUCUGGACCCUGGCUUCUCCCCACUGUAACGCCUGUUACACACAAACUGUUGUGGGUUCCUGCCAGGCUUGAAGAAAAUGAUCUGAAUUUUUUCCUCCUUUUGGUUUUAUUUUGUUGGUUUAUUUUGUGUUUUCUUUUCUCCUUUUUGGGGGGUAUUCAGAGUGGGCUGGGCCCCUGGGCGAGACACAGCUACCUCUGUUGGCAUCUUUUUAAUACCAGGAACCCAGCGGCUCUAGCCACUGAGCGGCUAAAUGAAAUAAAGUGGAAAAAAAAAAAAAGGAAAAAACCAAAAGCAUAAAAAACCACAGCAAAUUUCUUGAUGAAAAUUGAAAAUAAAAGUUUCCUUGUAUUUUA